ACUUGUGGCUCUGCCGCUCUAGCCCCCGGCGGAGCCAGCUGCUGCUCUUCGGUGCUGGCCCCGGUGCCGGCCCCGUUGCCCAGGGAACAGGCUCCCGGCAGCCCCCGCGGCCCGGAGUCCAUCCCGCCUCCUCCGGCCCGGCGGGGCCGACGAGUCCGGAGGGGCUGCCGCGGGAGCCCCCAGGUUUCCCUAGAUGACAAAUAAACAUUCCUUUUCCUGCGUGAAGAUAGUCUGUGGAAACCUUGGCCAUGGCAUCGAUAUCAGAGCCUGUUACAUUCAGAGAGUUCUGCCCGUUGUACUAUCUCCUCAAUGCCAUUCCGACAAAGAUCCAGAAGGGUUUCCGCUCUAUCGUGGUCUAUCUCACGGCCCUCGACACCAACGGGGACUACAUCGCGGUGGGCAGCAGCAUCGGCAUGCUCUAUCUGUACUGCCGGCACCUCAACCAGAUGAGGAAGUACAACUUUGAGGGGAAGACGGAAUCUAUCACUGUGGUGAAGCUGCUGAGCUGCUUUGAUGACCUGGUGGCAGCAGGCACAGCCUCUGGCAGGGUUGCAGUUUUUCAACUUGUAUCUUCAUUGCCAGGGAGAAAUAAACAGCUUCGGAGAUUUGAUGUCACUGGUAUUCACAAAAAUAGCAUUACAGCUCUGGCUUGGAGCCCCAAUGGAAUGAAAUUGUUCUCUGGAGAUGACAAAGGCAAAAUUGUUUAUUCUUCUCUGGAUCUAGACCAGGGGCUCUGUAACUCCCAGCUGGUGUUGGAGGAGCCAUCUUCCAUUGUGCAGCUGGAUUAUAGCCAGAAAGUGCUGCUGGUCUCUACUCUGCAAAGAAGUCUGCUCUUUUACACUGAAGAAAAGUCUGUAAGGCAAAUUGGAACACAACCAAGGAAAAGUACUGGGAAAUUUGGUGCUUGUUUUAUACCAGGACUCUGUAAGCAAAGUGAUCUAACCUUGUAUGCGUCACGGCCCGGGCUCCGGCUAUGGAAGGCUGAUGUCCACGGGACUGUUCAAGCCACGUUUAUCUUAAAAGAUGCUUUUGCCGGGGGAGUCAAGCCUUUUGAACUGCACCCGCGUCUGGAAUCCCCCAACAGUGGAAGUUGCAGCUUACCUGAGAGGCACCUGGGGCUUGUUUCAUGUUUCUUUCAAGAAGGCUGGGUGCUGAGUUGGAAUGAAUAUAGUAUCUAUCUCCUAGACACAGUCAACCAGGCCACAGUUGCUGGUUUGGAAGGAUCCGGUGAUAUUGUGUCUGUUUCGUGCACAGAAAAUGAAAUAUUUUUCUUGAAAGGAGAUAGGAACAUUAUAAGAAUUUCAAGCAGGCCUGAAGGAUUAACAUCAACAGUGAGAGAUGGUCUGGAGAUGUCUGGAUGCUCAGAGCGUGUCCACGUGCAGCAAGCGGAGAAGCUGCCAGGGGCCACAGUUUCUGAGACGAGGCUCAGAGGCUCUUCCAUGGCCAGCUCCGUGGCCAGCGAGCCAAGGAGCAGGAGCAGCUCGCUCAACUCCACCGACAGCGGCUCCGGGCUCCUGCCCCCUGGGCUCCAGGCCACCCCUGAGCUGGGCAAGGGCAGCCAGCCCCUGUCACAGAGAUUCAACGCCAUCAGCUCAGAGGACUUUGACCAGGAGCUUGUCGUGAAGCCUAUCAAAGUGAAAAGGAAGAAGAAGAAGAAGAAGACAGAAGGUGGAAGCAGGAGCACCUGUCACAGCUCCCUGGAAUCGACACCCUGCUCCGAAUUUCCUGGGGACAGUCCCCAGUCCUUGAACACAGACUUGCUGUCGAUGACCUCAAGUGUCCUGGGCAGUAGCGUGGAUCAGUUAAGUGCAGAGUCUCCAGACCAGGAAAGCAGCUUCAAUGGUGAAGUGAACGGUGUCCCACAGGAAAAUACUGACCCCGAAACGUUUAAUGUCCUGGAGGUGUCAGGAUCAAUGCCUGAUUCUCUGGCUGAGGAAGAUGACAUUAGAACUGAAAUGCCACACUGUCACCAUGCACAUGGGCGGGAGCUGCUCAAUGGAGCGAGGGAAGAUGUGGGAGGCAGUGAUGUCACGGGACUCGGAGAUGAGCCGUGUCCUGCAGAUGAUGGACCAAAUAGCACACAGUUACCCUUCCAAGAACAGGACAGCUCUCCUGGGGCGCAUGAUGGGGAAGACAUCCAACCCAUUGGCCCCCAAAGCACUUUUUGUGAAGUCCCCCUCCUGAACUCACUCACUGUGCCUUCCAGCCUCAGCUGGGCCCCAAGUGCUGAACAGUGGCUGCCUGGGACCAGAGCUGAUGAAGGCAGCCCCGUGGAGCCCAGCCAAGAGCAGGACAUCCUAACCAGCAUGGAGGCCUCUGGCCACCUCAGCACAAAUCUCUGGCAUGCUGUCACUGAUGAUGACACAGGUCAGAAAGAAAUACCCAUUUCUGAACGUGUCUUGGGGAGUGUGGGAGGACAGCUGACUCCGGUCUCUGCCUUGGCAGCCAGCACUCACAAGCCCUGGCUUGAGCAGCCUCCACGGGAUCAGACAUUGACGUCCAGCGAUGAGGAGGACAUCUAUGCCCACGGGCUUCCUUCUUCAUCCUCAGAGACGAGUGUGACAGAGCUCGGACCUAGUUGCUCCCAGCAGGACCUGAGCCGGCUGGGUGCAGAGGACGCCGGGCUGCUCAAGCCAGAUCAGUUUGCAGAAAGCUGGAUGGGCUACUCGGGUCCCGGCUAUGGCAUCCUCAGCUUGGUGGUCUCCGAGAAGUAUAUCUGGUGCCUGGACUACAAAGGCGGCCUGUUCUGCAGCGCGUUGCCGGGCGCCGGGCUGCGCUGGCAGAAGUUUGAAGAUGCUGUCCAGCAGGUGGCAGUCUCGCCCUCAGGAGCCCUUCUCUGGAAGAUUGAACAGAAAUCUAACCGGGCUUUUGCUUGUGGGAAAGUCACCAUCAAGGGGAAGCGGCACUGGUACGAAGCCCUGCCCCAGGCAGUGUUUGUGGCCCUGAGCGAUGACACGGCCUGGAUCAUCAGGACCAGUGGGGACCUAUACUUGCAGACAGGUCUGAGCGUGGAUCGCCCUUGUGCCAGAGCCGUAAAGGUGGACUGUCCCUACCCGCUGUCCCAGAUCACAGCCCGGAACAAUGUGGUGUGGGCGCUGACAGAGCAGAGGGCCCUCCUGUACCGGGAGGGCGUGAGCAGCUUCUGUCCGGAAGGCGAGCAGUGGAAGUGUGACAUUGUCAGCGAAAGGCAAGCUUUAGAACCCGUCUGCAUAACGCUCGGGGAUCAGCAGACUCUCUGGGCCCUGGACAUCCAUGGGAACCUGUGGUUCAGAACUGGCAUUAUUUCCAAGAAGCCCCAAGGAGAUGACGACCAUUGGUGGCAAGUGAGCAUCACGGACUAUGUGGUGUUUGACCAGUGCAGCUUAUUUCAGACGAUAAUCCAUGCCACUCACUCGGUGGCCACAGCAGCCCAAGCCCCCGUAGAAAAGGUGGCAGAUAAGCUGCGCAUGGCGUUUUGGUCCCAGCAGCUUCAGUGCCAGCCAAGCCUUCUCGGGGUCAAUAACAGCGGUGUCUGGAUCUCCUCGGGCAAGAAUGAAUUCCACGUCGCUAAGGGAAGUCUCAUAGGCACCUACUGGAAUCAUGUGGUUCCCCGUGGGACAGCUUCUGCUACAAAAUGGGCCUUUGUGUUGGCUUCUGCAGCUCCCACGAAGGAAGGAAGCUUCCUGUGGCUGUGCCAGAGCAGCAAGGACCUGUGCAGCGUCAGCGCCCAGAGCGCACAGUCGCGGCCCUCCACGGUGCAGCUGCCUCCCGAAGCCGAGAUGCGCGCCUAUGCCGCCUGCCAGGAUGCGCUGUGGGCGCUGGACAGCCUCGGCCAGGUGUUCAUCAGGACGCUCUCCAAGAGCUGCCCCACGGGCAUGCACUGGACCAGGCUGGACCUCUCCCAGCUAGGAGCUGUAAAAUUGACAAGCUUGGCAUGUGGAAAUCAGCACAUCUGGGCCUGUGAUUCCAGGGGUGGAGUUUACUUCCGUGUAGGGACUCAGCCUCUCAAUCCCAGUCUCAUGCUUCCAGCCUGGAUAAUGAUUGAGCCACCUGUCCAGCCCGCCGGGGUCAGCUUGGUCAGCGUCCAUUCCAGCCCCAACGACCAGAUGCUGUGGGUGCUUGACAGCAGGUGGAACGUGCACGUGCGGACCGGGAUCACCGAGGAGAUGCCUGUGGGGACCGCCUGGGAGCAUGUGCCAGGGUUGCAGGCCUGCCAGCUGGCGCUGAGCACCAGGACCGUGUGGGCCCGCUGUCCAAACGGAGACCUCGCCCGGCGGUACGGCGUCACAGACAAGAACCCCGCCGGGGACUACUGGAAGAAAAUUCCCGGCAGCGUGUCGUGUUUCACAGUGACUGCGUCAGAUGAGCUGUGGGCUGUGGGCCCGCCCGGCUACCUCCUCCAACGGCUGACAAAGACGUUCAGCCACUCGCACGGCACCCAGAAGAGCAGCCAGGCCGCCAUGCCCCACCCUGAGGACCUGGAGGACGAGUGGGAGGUCAUCUGAAGGAGCCCUGGCCGAGUCACGCGGAGGGGCCCGGCGUCUGUGGCGGGCACAGGGGCUUCAGAGUGACUCCCUGGUGGACGCGCUGCCUCAACACUUGUCCAGACACCUCUGGCCAGGUUGGACCCGCACACUUACUUUCAUCUAUGUUGGUUUCUGUCUCGUUCCAGAACCCACAGCCUCCACCCGUGGCUGGCGUGAUUGCUGCAGCAGUGGCGCCUCCUAGCUCAGGACAGUGGCGACUGCCCGGCUGCAUGCACUCCGAUUACCCACGUGCUGCCGUCCUGGUCUCAUCCACAGAUAGCUCCAGCUUUUGUUGGUGGGAGUGGUCUCCGGAGGCCUCCCAGAACCAAGGGUAGCCGGGCAGCUGGUUUGGCCCAGGGCCUCCUUCCACAUUAGUAGCCCCAGGGCCAGAUGGAGCCAAAGGUCAGCUCUCUGCAGCGCGGGAUGUGCUCGGUGAUGGCUUUGUCCCAUCAUAGGGGGGUGUCCCCCCAGAGACAAAGCUGCAGAGCACAUUCCAUGCCAGACGCUCUGGCCAGGAAGCUGAGGCCGGGCUUGAGAGGAGAGCGCUGGCCAUGCCAGGAGAGAACCCACGCACAUGCACACCACAACACACAACACACCUCACCUCACACCACAGCACACCUCACCACACCACACCGCACUGCACCAUACCUCACCACAUCUCACCACACCACAGCACACCUCACCACACAACACACCACACCCCACACCGCACUGCACCGCACCGCACCGCACCGUACCUCGCCACAUCUCACCACACCACACCACACCACACCUCACUGCCCACACACGGCGCAGGCUGCCCGCCUCCUGGAGAGCACACUUCAGCUGAAACAGUAAAGCCUGAUGGGUGCAAAUGGAACCUGGAUGUGUGCACGUGUGUCCCAGGUAGGGACGGCACAGGAGGGUGCAUGGGGCGUGGGGGAGCUGAGCAAGGGUCGCUCACUUAGAAAUGUCUUUGGAAUGGUGUUUAACUAAUGCUGCUGGCGGACAUCCUAAAACCAGAUGCAUCCUCAGAGGACGAGUCUACUAAUUAUUGCCUUUGUUGUUGUAUUACAAAUCUGCAUAAAAUACCUCAUUUCAAAUCAAAUCUUACAAAUUUAGAAGAGAGAUAUGUUUUCCGAAAACAGUGGAAGCCCUUUGUUCCUUCCCGGGUUUGUCCUGAGCCUGCACUGUCCUCGCCUGCAGCCUCAGAGGGGCAGGCAUCCCCGCACAGACUUGACUGGCAGGGCGGUCACGGGACCUGCGGGCUGGCUCCGAGUGGCAGCCCAUGCCUUCUGCGGGGUAUGGGUUGACACUUGACAGGUUGAAACCAGUGCCUCUAUGGACGGCUGCUGUGGCCCCUUCAGACAAUGGGCAGUGCCCACCCCGCCCACUGGCAUCUGCGUGUGAGGGCUAGGCCGCCCUGCCACACAUCCCGCCCCCUCCCGGAGGCAGCUUCAGGACAGGACACCAGGCUGGCUGCUUUUUUUAGCCUGCCCCUGGCCCAGGCCCAGUCCUUGGUGUCAGGGAGCCCCCAGGCCGCAGGUGGAGGGUGAUAAAAUAUGUUCUCUGACAGGACCCAGCCAGCCACAUAGGUGGAGGUUUUCCAUGUCCAAAUGAGGUCAAGAUGCCGAAAUCCCAGAUCUGACUUCACACUUCCCUUUUCUAGAACCUUUUGUAAAAGUUGGUGGCAGCAGAGGCAGCCCCAGGCCGGGCUGCAUCUCUCUGUGUCUGUUGUGCCUUGCCCGGCGCCUCACGGAUGGCAAAGCUCUCCUCACCCAUGGGACUGUAGUGCAAUUAAACCCGCGUCUAGGUGAUGCUUUUAAAGUUGUAGCUUCGUGCUUUGUACAGUUUUCUUUCUGGUUUUAAUUUUUAGUUGUGCUUUGAGUCAGUGCAAUAAACUAGACUUUUUCCAAACCUGGCCGAGUGUGGUGCCUGAGCUGUGAGAAGUGUCCUCAGCCGACACUCACGAGGGCAGUGCAAGGGAGAACCUGCCAGCCCAGCCCCACCACAGGGAGAGUGCGUCAGCAGACCUGUCCUGGCCUGGCUGGUGUUGAAAUACACACCGGUUUGCCCAAGUGGCUGUUAUGGGGGAAUGGCCGCUCCAGAGCUGGCUGUACCCCAUGGUAGCCUCUGAGGAGGACGCUGUGGGGUGAGGUCCAGGGCUGCCUCCUCAUGGAGCUGUGUGUGAGCAGGCGUUGGAGGGGUUCGAGCCCCUGGUUCUGUAUCUUCAGCCAGCAAACGAAACCAUAUCGCAAACCAGAGCUGCUGGAAACCAGCACACGCAAAAGAUGACGCCCAGCACAGCAGCAGGACACACCAUGUGCCAGGAAAUGACCUCAGCAAGAAACCUCAGGCCGUGUGAAGAGCAGCAAAGCUUUCCAGAAGGCAUAAAAGGAAACUUGAAUAAAGGAAGAUAUGUUCCACAUUCCUGGAUGGAGGACUACACACAUUAUGGAAAGACCUCAUUCUUUCCAAAGGAAUUUAUAGGUGUAGCUUGAUUUCAGUUCAAAUCCCCACUGGGAUUGUUUUGUUGGGGCAGGCAGGGAGGAAUAAUGUUAGUACCCACAAAUGCCCAUGACUGUGCCCAAUGUGCUUCUCACCAGAGCCCUGCAAGGGGAAGUCUCAUUAGCCCCUUGAGACUCAGAGAGGUUAGGUAACUUGCUCAAGGUCACACAGCACUGGGACUGGAAGCCAGCUCUGUAGAACUGCAGACCUGUGCUGUUUGAUGCCUCCUCACUGUCCCGUCACUCCUGGGAAGAAGAAACGGGUGAGAACUGCUAAGUGAUGACAGGUGGAGCCCCAGCAGGGGCCACUCUAUUGAAUGGCAUGGCCCAGACCCUCGGAGGGCCAGGCAACAGGCUAGCAAGGCCCACAGGGAGGGAGCAGAAUGGAGAGGGCAUCUCAGAUGCGCUUAAGGAGCGGCGGGGGCGGGGCAUGGGGGGUGUCACAACUAAUGUGGCCACUGCUUCAUUCUCUGGGCAAAAUAAUAUUAAAUGGAUUAAAGAAUCUAAAACCAGUGGGAAAACUGUCUGAUUUCUGGAUGGCAAAGGCUUUCUAAACUCAAAAGUGAUAGGACAAGCUACAGAGGAAAAUAAGUACAUAGAUUUGAUUUCUCCAAAAUACAGAAAUGCUGCUGGGCACAGUGAUGUGCAGUUAUAGUCCCAGCUACUUGGGAGGCCAAGGCAGGAGGAUUACUUGAGCCCAGGAGUUUGAGGCUGCAAUGAACUAUGAUCACACCACUGCACUCCAGCCUCGGCGACAGAGCAAGACCUUGUUUCUCAAAAAUAAAUAAAUAGAAGGAAAUAAAUGUAAAAAUGCUGCAAAUUAAAAACCUCAAAGAAGGGAAAUAAUUGCAACAAAUGGGAAUUGAUGUUGAAUAUUUACCUUAAAAACCUAUACAACAAUAAGAGGAGUGCGCCCUUCAGCAGCAUGUAUACAAAAAUUGCAACGAUACAGAGAUUAGCAUGGCCCCUGCACAAGGAUGACUCGCAAAUUCAUAAAGCUUUCCAUAAAUAUAUUUAUUAAAAACCAAUAGGAGGAGCACUUCGAGUCGAGUGUAAGGGCCCUUCACAAAAGCAGAAGGAACACUGGCCCAAACCCCCAGCACCCCGGAAGCAGAGGUGAGAUGGGAGCAGCUUGGGAGCCCCCCAUUGGCGCCGCCCUACUGGGGAAGCCGGUCCGUACGUAGGCCUUGCAUCUCGCCACCUCCACUUCUGUCCUCAAGAACAAGUCCUAGGUCAAGGGAAACAGCACAGCCUGUUUAUAAUUAGGAAACACUUAAAACAGCCUGGCAUUUGGGAACAGCCAUGUUAACGUGAGCAAAUUCCUCUCAUGAAAUAGCCUGCAGCUAUUAAGAAGCACGUGUGUGCAGGAAGCGGAGGCGCAGGACCUCACCGCGCCAGCGUGAAGUUCCCGGGCAUGGUCAUGAAAGCGUGGUUCUGUAAGAAAUCAGAGGGAGAAAGGGAGAGAAGGGGGAGGGAGACAACCCAAACGUUGGAGGGUAUUUGUUGUAAACUUCAAACUUUUGGCAGGUUUGAAAUUUUUCAUAACUCCGGGGAGGAGCAAGAGGGGUGAAAAGAAACAAGUUCUCUACUUGUGAUCAGCAGCUGGUCAUAGUGGUUGCCUGGAGUAUAUGCCUUUUUGUAUCCUUUGAAUUUCCAGCCAUGUAAAUGUAUUAUUUAUUCCAAAAAUAAAGCAGAUUUACAUUUUAAAAA